GCUGUCCUGGCUCGGGAGAUGGACGGCCGCCGUGUUUUGGGCCGGUUCUGGAGUGGCUGGCGGCGGGGCCUGGGUGUCCGCCCAGUGCCCGAGGACGCAGGCUUUGGCACCGAAGCCCGGCAUCAGAGGCAACCCCGCGGCUCCUGCCAACGGUCGGGGCCCCUCGGGGACCAGCCCUUCGCGGGGCUGCUGCCAAAAAACCUCAGUCGGGAGGAGCUGGUUGAUGCGCUGCGGGCAGCCGUGGUGGACCGGAAAGGACCUCUAGUGACGUUGAACAAGCCACAGGGUCUACCAGUGACAGGAAAACCAGGAGAGCUGACGUUGUUCUCAGUGCUGCCAGAGCUGAGCCAGUCCCUAGGGCUCAGGGAGCAGGAGCUUCAGGUUGUCCGAGCAUCUGGGAAAGAAAGCUCUGGGCUUGUACUCCUCUCCAGCUGUCCCCAGACAGCUAGUCGCCUCCAGAAGUACUUCACCCAUGCACGGAGAGCCCAAAGGCCCACAGCCACCUACUGUGCUGUCACUGAUGGGAUCCCAGCUGCUUCUGAGGGGAAGAUCCAGGCUGCCCUGAAACUGGAACACAUUGAUGGGGUCAAUCUCGCUUGUUCACUCUUGGCUGGCACCACAGACAGUUCCAGUGAAGGCCCCAUCCCGAAAGGACAUCCUGGAAGGUGUCAAGAAGACUCUCAGUCACUUUCGUGUGGUAGCCACAGGCUCUGGCUGUGCCCUGGUCCAGCUGCAGCCACUGACAGUGUUCUCCAGUCAACUACAGGUGCACAUGGUACUACAGCUCUGCCCUGUGCUUGGGGACCACAUGUACUCUGCCCGUGUGGGCACUGUCCUGGGCCAGCGAUUUCUGCUGCCAGCUGAGAACAACAAGCCCCAAAGACAGGUCCUGGAUGAAGCCCUCCUCAGACGCCUCCACCUGACCCCCUCCCAGGCUGCCCAGCUGCCCUUGCACCUCCACCUACAUCGGCUCCUUCUCCCAGGCACCAGGGCCAGGGACACCCCUGUUGAGCUCCUGGCACCACUGCCCCCUUAUUUCUCCAGGACCCUACAGUGCCUGGGGCUCCGCUUACAAUAGUCCUCCCUCUGUUCCUGACCCCCUCACACACACUGGAAAGUGAGGGUGGGGGCUCUGCAGUCAGACAAACCUAAGAUCACAUCCUGGACAGGCCACUUGCUUGCUGUGUGGCAUUGGGCAAGUAACUUUACCUCUCUGGACUUGUGAUAAUAAAAGUUCCUACCUCA